GCCAGGAAAGCAGAGACAGACAAAGCGUUAGGAGAAGAAGAGAGGCAGGGAAGACAAGCCAGGCACGAUGGCCACCUUCCCACCAGCAACCAGCGCCCCCCAGCAGCCCCCAGGCCCGGAGGACGAGGACUCCAGCCUGGAUGAAUCUGACCUCUAUAGCCUGGCCCAUUCCUACCUCGGGCCUCUCAUCAUGCCUAUGCCCACUUCACCUCUGACUCCUGCCUUGGUUACAGGAGGUGGAGGCCGGAAAGGUCGCACCAAGAGAGAAGCUGCUGCCAACACCAACCGCCCCAGCCCUGGCGGGCACGAGAGGAAACUGGUGACCAAGCUGCAGAAUUCAGAGAGGAAGAAGCGAGGGGCACGGCGCUGAGACAGAGCUGGAGAUGAGGCCAGACCAUGGACACUACACCCAGCAAUAGAGACGGGACUGCGGAGGAAGGAGGACCCAGGACAGGAUCCAGGCCGGCUUGCCACACCCCCCACCCCUAGGACUUAUUCCCGCUGACUGAGUCUCUGAGGGGCUACCAGGAAAGCGCCUCCAACCCUAGCAAAAGUGCAAGAUGGGGAGUGAGAGGCUGGGAAUGGAGGGGCAGAGCCAGGAAGAUCCCCCAGAAAAGAAAGCUACAGAAGAAACUGGGGCUCCUCCAGGGUGGCAGCAACAAUAAAUAGACACGCACGGCAGCCACAGCUUGGGUGUGUGUUCAUCCUUGUUCUUUGUGUGUUUUUGUUCGGGCAUGUGUGUGCUUGCCUGUGCCUGCACAUUCAUGAGCCUGAGAGAGCAUCUUUGAUGUGUAUUUGUGUUUGGUGUAUGUAUCUGGGGCAGGGAGUGUUCCUGCUCUUGCAGGGUCUACGCUGUGAAUGCAGCUUUUGGUUUGUUUGCUUUUGCUUGCAUAUAUUUUAGUGCAUACAUUUCUGUGGGCUCCUACGUAGUGGAAAGGAAUUUCUUCUGCUUUUUUGCGAUACUGCCCAUGAAACACGGCCCUCCCCAGCACCUGUUUUUGUUGAUUGUGUCCUGUUCAUAGACGGGAACGCUACUUAUGAGUGCCAUCUAAAAGUCAGAGAAAACUGAGAUUUAAAAUAUUAAAAGCCAGGGCCGGGGGCAGUGGCUCACGCCUGUAAUCCCAGCACUUUGGGAGGCCGAGGUGGGUGGAUCACAAAGUCAGGAGUUCAAGACCAGCCUGACCAACAUGGUGAAACCCCAUCUCCACUAAAAAUACCAAAAAUUAGCCAAGCAUGGUGGCAGGUGCCUGUAAUCCCAGCUGCUCAGGAGGCUGAGGCAGUAGAAUCGCUUGAACCCAGGAGGUAGAGGUUGCAGUGAGCCGACAUCGUGCCAUUGCACUCCAGCCUGGGUGACAGAGGGAGACUCUGUCUCAAAACAAACAAACAAACAAAAACUAAAGUCUGGGAGCAGUGGCUCAUGCCUGUAAUCACAGCAGUUUAGGAGGCCGAAGUGGGAGGAUUACUUGAGCCUAGGAGUUUGAGACCAGCCUGAGCAUCAUAGUAAGACCCCAUCUCUACAAUUUUUUUUUUGAGACAGAGUCUCACUCUGUUGCUCAGGUUAGAGUGCAGUGGCACCAUCUUGGCUCACUGCAACCUCUGCCUCCCGGGUUCAAGCAAUUCUCGUGCCUACGCCCCCUGAGUAGCUGGGAUUACAGGUGAGCACCACCACGCCUGGCUAAUUUUUGUUUUUUUGUUUUUUUGAUACAGAGUCUCACUCUGUUGCUCAGGCUGGAGUGCAGUGGCAUGAUCGCAGCUCACUGCAACCUCCGCCUCCUGGGUUCAAGCUAUUCUCCUGCUUCAGCCUCCUGAGUAGCUGGGACUACAGGCACCUGCCACCAUGCCUGGCUAAUUUUUGUAUUUUUAGUAGAAACAGAGUUUCACCAUGUUGGCCAGGAUGGUCUCAAUCUCUUGACCUCAUGAUCCACCCACCUUGGCCUCCCAAAGUGCUGGGAUUACAGGCGUCAGCCACCACGCCUGGCCAAUUUUUGUAUUUUUAGUAGAGAUGGGGUUUCAUCAUGUUGGCCAGGCUGGUCUCAAACUCCUGGCCUCAAAUGAUCUGCCCACCUCAGCCUUCCAGCCUUUGGGAGGCCAAGGAGGGAGGAUCGCUUGAGGCCAGGAGUUCGAGACCAGCCUAGGCAACAUACCAAGGCCCUGUCUCUACAAAAAUUUAAAAAUUAGCAAAGCAUGGUGGCUCAUGCCUGUAGUCCUAGUUGCUCAGAGGCUGAAGUUGGAGGAUCCCUUGAACCCAGUUGGAGGCUACAGUAAGCCAUGAUGGUGCCACUGCACUGCAGCCUGAGCAAUAGAGUGAAACCAUGUAUUGAAAAAGAAAGAAAGAAAGAAAGAGAAAAAGAAGGAAGGAAGGAAAAGAAAGGAAGGAAGAAAGAAAAGAAAGAGAGAAAGGAGAGAAAAAGAAGAAAGAGAGAGAAAGAGAAGAAAGAAAGAAAGAAAGAAAGAAAGAAAGAAAGAAAGAAAGAAAGAAAGGAAGGAAGGAAAGAAAGAAAGAAAGAAGGAAAGAAAGAAAGAAAGAAAGAAAGAAAGAAAGAAAGAAAAGAGCGAGCCCCGGCACAGUGGCUCACACCUGUAAUCCCAGCACUUUGGGAGGCCAAGGCAGGCGGAUCACCUGAGGUCAGUAGUUCGAGUUCGAGGCAGAAGUUGUGGUGAGCCAAGAUCACGCCAUUGCACUCCAGCCUGGGCAACAAGAGCAAAACUCCAUCUCAAAAAAAGAAAAAGAGAGAGAAAGAAAGAGAGAAGGAGGGAAAGAAAGAGGAAGGAAAGGAGGGAGGGAAGGAGGGAAGGAGGAAAGGAGGGAAGGAAAUAUUAAGGGAUUUGCCCUAGCUCACUCAGGGCUCAUAUUCAGGGAUCUUAUUGUCUUCAGAUAUGAGGUGGGUCCCCAGGCCAAGGGGGCUGUGGGACAGGGUUCUGGGAAGUGAGAUGGGGGAGGGAGAUUCUUAUUCAGUGCUAUGUCUCAGGACCAGAGUUGAAGAAAAAUAUGGGGCAAACAGGAAGUGUGGUUGGAGCUGAGAUUAUUUGUUGAUUGAGAUACAGGUUUGGGUUGCUAUUAUGAAGAAUCAAAACAGGAUACAAAGUUACUCCUCUCUUACUUAGCCCCAAGUCCUCCUGGGUUCAAAUGGCAGCUCCAUUGUGUUGAGGAUUCCAGCUAUUUUUACUCACUGUUCUGCCACACCCAAAACAUGGCUUCCACUUUGAGGCCCAAAAUAGCUACUCCAAUACCUGCCAUCACGUUUGCAUCUCAGCCUGUGGAAAGAGUGUGGAAGAGACAGAGGAGGCCACACCUCUUCAAUUUUAGGGCAUAAUCUAAAAGUAGAACACAUCACAUCUGCUCCGAAUGUGGCUACAUGGCCACACCCAACUACGAGAGAGGUUGGGAAAUGUAGCAUUGAGCUGCUUAGCCACGUGGUAGCCAAAACUUGGGCAACAGCAGGGUUUUAUGAUGAAAGGGAACCAGAGAGAGUGAAUACACGAAGAAGCUAGCAAGAAACAUUGCCCACAUGCAGACUCAACAGAUGUCGGGGGAGAAAACUCUGAGAUUGGGCCCCGGGCAGAGCCUGUUUCCUUUUCCCCUGUCCCUUUCACAUAAGCCCCACACUGCAGAACUUGGAGUCAGUGGUUCAUGGGGACCCAAGGACAUCCACAGAAGACCGAAGUACCUGAUAGAGCAGGAACAGAUGCACGUCAGACUACGACCAGCUUGAACCCUUGGGGACCUGUAUCCAUCCCCUUCCCUUGAGUCCAGCCUAAUCACAGCCACAGAAUGAAUCCAUGACCCGGAAGGACAUUUAAGGACCUCUGGCCCAACUCUCCCCACGCAACAGUGGGAUUGCCUCUGCUUGUUUGAAUACCACUAUGGAGGGGGAACUUGCUACAUUUAAAGGUUGCUGAAUUUUUUUGUUUUGUUUUGGGAGAUGGAGUCUCUCUCUGUCGCCCAGGCUGGAGUGCAGUGGUGUGAUCUCGACCCACUGCAACCUCCGCUUCCUGGGUUCAAGCGAUUUUCAUGCCUCAGCCUCCCUAGUAGCUGGGACUACAGGUGUGGGCCACCACACCUGGCUAAUUUUUGUAUUUUUAGUAGAGACGGGGUUUCACCAUGUUGCCCAGGCUGGUCUCAAACUCCCGACCUCAGGUGAUCUGCCUGCCUUGGCCUCCCAAAGUGUUGGGAUUACAGGCUUGAGCCACACCACCCGGCAAAGGUUGCCUAAUUCUAUCUCAGGGCAAGUCUGUUCAUGUGGGCUGAAAUCUGUCUCUCAUACCUGCCCUUAAAUAAGCUUCUGUUUUUCUGGUCCUUUCUGUCUGAGAUGACUUUAAUUCCUCCCCCGACCCCAUCUCAUGAGGCUCAGCUUAGAUGUUUCCUUCUCUUCCUCCCUGAUGGCUGCGUGCAGAAGCUCAUACCUGCAAUCCCAGCACUUUGGGAGGCCGAGGUGGGAGGAUUGCUUGGGCCCAGGAGUUCUAGGCCAGCCUAGCAACACAGCAAGACCCUCUCUCUACAAAAAAUUAAAAAUUAGCCAGGUGUGGUGGCUUGUGCCUGUGGGCCCACCUACUCAGGAGGCUGAGGUGAGAGGAUCUCUUGAGUCUGGGAGGUGGAGGCUGCAGUGAGCCAUGAUCUCACUCCAGCCUGGGCGUCAGAGUGAGACCUGUCUCAAAAAAACAAAAACCAAAGUUUUCCUUAACUUGCAAUCCUCCACCCAUCUCCUGACCUCCACCCCAGGCCGACCCUCCUCUGGGAUCACACGGAAGCCUGGGCCCAGAAUCUUACAGUCUACCUUGGAAAUCCUUCAGAUUUUGCCUCCAACUCCUCUUUCCAUACAAGUUACAUAUUAACUCAAUCAAUGCUUAUUGGAUGCCUUCUGAGUUACCAGGAUGCUGCUGGAGGCCUGUGCUGCUGAGAGGGACAAAUAGAAUCCUGAUAUGACUGGAACCAGGAAUAGGGCCACCAUCAGCUCUAGAACCCAGGGAGCAAAUGGCAGGAGCAACACCAGGCAGUCGGCCCUCAGCCCAGCACAGACCUGGUGUGUUGGCUUCAGAAAAUCCUGGAAACAUCUCUGCUGUGUUUGGAGCUCCUAUUCUGUGAGAAGUGUUUUAUAGGCUUUGCUCCAUUUAAUCCUUACGAUAACCCAAUAGGACAUACUAUUAAUGAUCCCCUUUUUUUCAGACCGGAAAACUGAGGUUCGGAGACAUUAAGUAAUUUGCCUAAAGUCACACAGCCACAUCCUGUAGGACUUGGAAUUAUGAACUCAGGUCUAUCUGAAUUUUAAAGCCUGGAUUUUUCCCCCUUUGCUACAUGCCUGGGAAGAACCAUGUAUUGACAAUGAAGAAUCCUAAACUCUCGUUAA